AAUCACCACUGGAGGCUCCCUCCCGAGGCACCCUCGCUGGCGAGCUGAGAGGAAAUGGCGGGGAGGUCCCUGACAUCGAAGGCCGAGCCCACCGCAGGAGCCGUGGACAGGGCUGAGAAGGCCGGAGGGCAGGACACGUCCUCACAGAAAAUUGAAGACUUGAUGGAAAUGGUGCAAAAGCUGCAGAAAGUGGGAAGCCUAGAGCCCCGAGUUGAGGUCCUGAUUAACCGGAUUAAUGAGGUCCAGCAAGCAAAAAAGAAAGCCAAUAAAGACCUAGGAGAGGCCCGGACCAUCUGUGAGGCCCUGCAGAAGGAACUGGACUCGCUGCAUGGAGAGAAAGUACACCUGAAGGAGAUCUUGAGCAAAAAACAAGAGACCCUGAGGAUCCUCCGGCUGCAUUGCCAGGAAAAGGAAAGUGAGGCACACAGGAAGCACACCAUGUUGCAGGAGUGCAAGGAGAGAAUUUCUGCCCUGAACUUGCAGAUUGAAGAAGAGAAGAACAAACAGAGACAGCUGAGGUUGGCAUUCGAGGAACAGCUGGAAGAUCUGAUGGGCCAGCACAAGGACCUCUGGGACUUCCACAUGCCAGAGCGGCUGGCAAAGGAGAUUUGUGCCCUGGACAGCAGCAAGGAGCAGCUGCUCAAGGAAGAGAAGCUGGUCAAGGCGACACUGGAAGACGUGAAGCAUCAGCUGUGCUCCCUGUGUGGGGCUGAGGGCCCCUCCACCCUUGAUGAGGGACUCUUUCUCCGCAGCCAGGAGGCUGCAGCCACAGUGCAGCUGUUUCAGGAAGAGCACAGGAAGGCUGAGGAGCUCCUAGCAGCUGCUGCCCAGCGCCACCAGCAGCUGCAGCAGAAGUGCCAACAACAGCAGCAGAAGCGGCAGAGGCUGAAGGAAGAGCUGGAAAAGCAUGGAAUGCAAGUCCCUGCCCAAGCCCAGAGCACACAAGAGGAAGAGGCUGGCCCAGGAGAUGUGGCUCCCAGACCAGGUAGACCAGUGACAUGGUGGAGUUGAAGAGAGAGGCUCACUGCAGAGCACUGUUUCCAUGGAAAAAUGGAACAUGGCAAAGUGCAGAAAUUCUUCAGUCAGUCCAGGACAGACGAGUUCUCUAAGAUGCAGUUAAUCAUACCUGUCUUAAACAAACUGGCAAUAUACUAUCAAACAUGACUUUUAAAUCAAGUGGAAGUUAGAAAAUAUAUUGAACUGAGUGGCAAUGAAGACACCACAUUUUAAAACUGUAAUUCAGUUAAGCCCACAAUUAGAAGGAACUUUAGCUUUUAUUGGUUCACCACAAUUUUUUAAGAAAUCAACCAAUGAUUGUUCAGUUAAUGAAUAAAAGGCCUUUGACACAGUUCACCUAUUCAUGUGAAAAAAAAAGACUAAUAAAUAGUCAGCUUCCCUUAGA